UGGGCCUCUGUUCGUCCGUCCGACCCCCCUCAUGUGUGCUGCCCCAAACCUCGCCGCUCCCUAGUUUGGUAUUCUGUGUCCGGCCUGGGGUAGUAGCUGGACACCAGACUCAAUCUUGGGCUCCAGUUCCCGACUUUUCGCCUCCUCUGGGUCUGUCCUGGGGUCAGUAAUUAACCCGGGUCCCAGGGGUGUCGUCUUUUCCCUCCAGGGUGGGGCGCUGCCUGUACAUGCCAGGGAUCUUUUGCAGGGCUUUUCAUCCAGAUUUGCUUCAGGGUUGUCCGGGAUCGAUUUGGACUGGGCUCGGAACCGGUCCUGGAUACGUAGGUCGCUGUGGCACCAGCAUGCUCUGUAUCAUCUUUACUCACUUGAAAGCUUGCUGAAGCUGUUGUUGAAGUAAACUUAAAGAAAAAACUUGCUUAAGGAAAAUCAGUAGUUUAGACACCCCCUCCCCCGCCUUUUUUUGCAGACAUACUAAAAAAAAAAAGAUGCUUUUCUCUAAUCUACACUCUUAAUUCUUUUGGCUAUCUGAUGUCACAGUUGUAUGAUGAGUUCAUUCAGAGGCUGUACGAAUUGAUUUUAAAGAGUUGGACAGUUAUAUCCUUUCUCCCAAAGUUUGUUUACCUUCAUAUUUGGAACUGUCAUUUUUCUUAAGGAAAAAUUGUUCUUGGAUUUUCUUGAGAGAUUCCUUACACUGUUAAAAUUGUUGCUGCAAUGCAGAGUUUCACACAGGUGGGCAGAGAUGUUUUGUUUAAACUUAUUCCAUGAAGUGUUUACUUCGGAUAAACUGAGGAUUUCCUAGGGGAGAAAGUGAUGUAGGUAGGUUUAGUGAACAGAUUUUAGGUAGUAAACUUUACUGCUGAAAGGUUUGUAGGAAAUAUGGGUUUUCCACAAUAAAUGGUGAUUUAAAAACUUUUUAUAAGGGAAUGCAGUUACUGCAGAUUAUUGCUAUUAGCAGAUGGCCACUGUUUUUGCAGCGUAAAGUAUUCACAAAUCACCUUCUUGAAACCAGUGACGCUAUCUGCAACUCUCAUCUUGUGUGUAGAUUAGGGUUUAUUCUGUAGUUUUUUGGGUACUUAUGUCAUUCUCUUUCCUCCCACCCCUGAAAGGGGAGGUGGUAUCAUGAAUCAGGAAAAAUAGACUGAAGUGACAAGUUCAGUGAGCUUUUCCUAUGCAAAGGAAAAUUUAUUUCAAGGUUGUUGAUUUUGAACAGGCAAAGGGUAGAUGAUUUUUAAAGUCCUUGGAAAAAAUUGUGGAGAGAUUAGCUGCACAACUUUUCUUUUUCCUCUUCCUUUCUUUUCUUUUUUCUUUCUUUUCGAGACAGCCUCAUUCUGCUGCCCAGGCUGCAGCACAGUGGCCCCAUCAUAGCUCACUGCAGCCUCCAACUCCUGGACUCAAGCAGUCCUUCUGUCUCAGACUCCUGAGUGGCUAGGACUAUAGGCACCAACCACCACACCUGGCUAAUUUUUUUUUUUUUUUUUUUUGUAGAGCCGAGGUUUCACUAUGUUGCCCAGGCUGGUCUUGAACUCCUGGGCUCAAGUGAUCCUCCCAUCUCGGCCUUCCAAAGUGCUGGGAUUACAGUUGUGAGCCACCAUCCCCAGCAUAUUUGCACAACUUUUAAAUUUAGAUAGAAACUGUAGCUUCUUCCACAUGUGAAGUACUUAAUUAUUUAGAGCAUAAGAUUGGAAUAUUGGAAUUGAGAGAAUCUGGAAAAAUAGUUAAGUUAGAUGUAGUUACAGAUUUGCAGGUAUGACAAUGUAUUUUUAAGGGAAAUACUUCAAGAGUUUUAAGAGCAGAGAAAGGUGAUUGGGGAAAAUCAGAUACUGAUUGUAUUUUUAUAUUAUACAAGUCAAUUCAACAAACACUGAGCAUUUGCUAUGCAUGUUAUGCUAUGUUAUGCAUAGCAUGCUAUUUGCUAUGCUAUGUUAGGUAACUAUGUAAGGAGCAAAUAAAGGUAUAGCCAUAACAGUUGAGUUUCAUGUUUUGGUAAUAAUUUCUGAAAUCAUGAAGAGUUGAGUUGUAUUCUUUAGGCAUACUAACAAUUUUUUUUGUAAUUGGGACUUAACAUUGGCGAUGGGUGUUGAGUGCUUCAUGAAAAGCGCUAUACUAGGCAUUUUAGGAUAUAAAGAUUAAACUUUUGGUUUUUAGGAAUUUGAAAUCUAGAAGGGGAUAUAAGAUUUGUGUAAACAUUUACAACAUAAACAUUUGUAAAUACUUAUGGGUGGUUUGAGGUAAAGUUUGGAGUAAAUUAUACAAAAGAAGAAAGGGUUCAUUUUUAGCUUAAGUAAUGGAAAUUUGUGGAGAUAGCUCAGAAGCUACUGUUUAUUGAGCAUUUACUGAACAGACUUAAUGCUAGUUGCUGUUUACAGCAUUUUCUUAGCUUCACAGCAAUAUGUAAGUACCUUAAUAAUGAGGACAGUGAGGCUCAAAUAUGUUAAGUUACUUGCCUGGGCUAUGUGGCUAGCAUGUAACAGCCCCAAUUUGAAUCCAAAUCUGUCUGGUGCCAAAGCCUGUGUGUUUCUACUGCAUCAUGUUGCUCCCCAAUAAACUGGUAACCUGAGUUUAAUGUUACAGAGAAUAAGACUUUUCUAAGACAAAGAUUUAUGGAUUGGGAGUAGGUGGGUGAAGAAGGCCUUUCAAAUAAAGAGAAUGAUGUGAGCAGAAGUGUGGAGGUGGGAAAGUUCAUUGUGUACUUGGAGAAAAGUUAGUGGACCAGAUUACCUGGAAUAUACUGUUCAUUUUUGGGAAUUAGAGAUGAGGUUUGAAUUUUAAGUGGGGGCAGGAUUGUGGAGCAUGUUUAAGUGCUGCUUUUAGAAGUUUGACAUUUGGGGAAAAAAAGUUCGACGUUUGGGAGGUAAUGAGAAGUUACCAAGGUCUAAUAGAGUAGUGUGCAGAAUGAUUUGAUGUGGAAAGCUGACUUUCAAUGUAGUAUAAAUACUGGGCAAGGGCAGUGGUAAUGGAAUUAGAGUGAAGGCUCUGCAGGACCUCAAUGUCGUAGGUGGGUGGCGAGGAGGAGGGGUUUUUGGAGCAGGUUUGGAGGAGAUGGAAGGUGAAGAUUACACUUUUGUUUUUGAGACAGAGUCUAGCUUUGUUGCCAGGCUGGAGUGCGGUGGCGUGAUCUUGGCUCACUGCAACCUCCGCCUCCUGGGUUCAAGUGAUUGUCCUGCUUCAUCUUCCCGAAUAGCUGGGACUACAGGUGCUCACCACCACGCCCAGCUAACUUUUGUAUUUUUAGUAGAGACGGGGUUUCACCAUGUUGACCAGGAUGGUCUCGAUCUCUUGACCUCGUGAUCCGCCUGCCUCAGCCUCCCAAAGUGCUGGGAUUACAGGUGUGAGCCACUGCGCCCAGCUGAAGAUUACACUUUUUAAGUGUCGGAGAUGUUGACGGUGGUACUCUUACUAGAAAUACGGGCAAGGAGAAAUGACCAUUAAGAAGUAGAUGCCCAGAUGCAAAAGUGAUGAAACAGUCCAUUUGUCAUAAAGUAAGAUGCAGCUGUGGCAUGUCAACCAGCUUGGAACAAAAUUGUAUCUGUUUUUCUCAGAAGAGAAUUCCACAAGGUUAAAUCAGCAAACAAAGAAAACAUGGUAUUUUGAAAUAUGAUUAAACUCCUGAUGCUGCAGCAGAGGCUAAGAAUAUUAAUGGCCAGAUCUAGUGCACACAUGGUCUUCUGAAGAAGCCAUGGGUAGCUGUUGUAGCUGUCCAGAUAAAGACACUGUCCCAGAUAACCAUCGGAACAAGUUUAAGGUCAUUAAUGUGGAUGAUGAUGGGAAUGAGUUAGGUUCUGGCAUAAUGGAACUUACAGACACAGAACUGAUUUUAUACACCCGCAAACGUGACUCAGUAAAAUGGCACUACCUCUGCCUGCGACGCUAUGGCUAUGACUCGAAUCUCUUUUCUUUUGAAAGUGGUCGAAGGUGUCAAACUGGACAAGGAAUCUUUGCCUUUAAGUGUGCCCGUGCAGAAGAAUUAUUUAACAUGUUGCAAGAGAUUAUGCAAAAUAAUAGUAUAAAUGUGGUGGAAGAGCCAGUUGUAGAAAGAAAUAAUCAUCAGACAGAAUUGGAAGUCCCUAGAACACCUCGAACACCUACAACUCCAGGAUUUGCUGCUCAGAACUUACCUAAUGGAUAUCCCCGAUAUCCCUCAUUUGGAGAUGCUUCAUCCCAUCCGUCAAGCAGACAUCCUUCUGUGGGAAGUGCUCGCCUGCCUUCAGUAGGGGAAGAAUCUACACAUCCUUUGCUUGUGGCUGAGGAACAAGUACAUACCUAUGUCAACACUACAGGUGUGCAAGAAGAGCGGAAAAACCGCACAAGUGUGCAUGUUCCAUUGGAGGCGAGGGUUUCUAACGCUGAAAGCAGCACACCAAAAGAAGAACCAAGUAGUAUUGAGGACAGGGAUCCUCAGAUUCUUCUUGAACCUGAAGGAGUCAAAUUUGUUUUAGGGCCAACCCCUGUUCAAAAGCAGUUAAUGGAAAAAGAGAAACUGGAGCAACUUGGAAGAGAUCAAGUUAGUGGAAGUGGAGCAAAUAACACAGAAUGGGACACUGGCUAUGACAGUGAUGAACGAAGAGAUGCACCCUCUGUUAACAAACUGGUGUAUGAAAAUAUAAAUGGGCUAUCUAUCCCUAGUGCCUCAGGGGUCAGGAGAGGUCGUCUGACAUCCACCAGUACCUCAGAUACCCAGAAUAUCAACAACUCAGCUCAGAGAAGAACUGCAUUAUUAAACUAUGAAAAUCUACCAUCUUUGCCUCCUGUUUGGGAAGCCCGCAAGCUAAGUAGGGAUGAAGAUGACAAUUUAGGACCAAAGACCCCAUCUCUAAAUGGCUACCAUAAUAAUCUAGAUCCAAUGCAUAACUAUGUAAAUACAGAGAAUGUAACAGUGCCAGCAAGUGCUCACAAAAUAGAAUAUUCAAGGCGUCGGGACUGUACACCAACAGUCUUUAACUUUGAUAUCAGACGCCCAAGUUUAGAACACAGGCAGCUUAAUUACAUACAGGUUGACUUGGAAGGUGGCAGUGACUCUGACAACCCUCAGACUCCAAAAACGCCUACAACUCCCCUUCCACAAACCCCUACCAGGCGCACAGAGCUGUAUGCCGUGAUAGACAUCGAGAGAACUGCUGCUAUGUCAAAUUUGCAGAAAGCACUGCCACGAGAUGAUGGUACAUCUAGGAAAACUAGACACAAUAGUACUGAUCUGCCCAUGUGAGCCUGGAAAGCAUUGUGUUGUUUGCACCUUUGUGAAGUUUUUAAAAAUGAAGAUGCAAGUGCUUCAUUUUCAUUUCUAAACACUAACUCCUUUUAUAGACUGAUAAAAUUUUUUUCUGAAUAUUUCAUGUGCAUCUUUAACUAAAGGGAAUUAAUGUAGAGCAGGUACUCCUUAAAGAACACUAAUUUCAUUAUAUACUACUCGUUGUACAGCAGCAUUCCCGUUUUCACAGUGCCUAUUUAAAAUGAGAGUUGAAGUAAAUGACAUGCUGGUUGAUUUUUAUCAAUAUUCUGGACUUAACGCAUACCUUUCAUGUCUAAGUCAUGGUUGGCUUUUAAAACUUUUUAUAAAGCCUCUUGACAAUGUACAUUGCUAACAGGUAACUAUAGGCUUUGAAAGUAAUGCUCGUAGAUUCAGUGUUCACAGUAUGUGGCCUCCAGCAUGUAACAUGAGGAAUCCUUUAUUUCAUUAAUUAAUGGCUUUUUGACUUGAGCCAAAACAUAUGUAAAGGAAACAGAAGUACCGCACCUCCUCUUACACCAGUCAGCUCCUUUGCCUUCAGUGUUACUAGAAAGCGGCCUGUGUCCAUGAGUGUGCUUUGCUGUUGGUGCACUGAAAGGCAGGAAGGAGACAAGAUUUUCUAUUUACUCAUCUCAUGAUGUCAUUUGAAGGGCAUGUCCAGAUAUCUUAAAAUUAUAAUAGGCUCAAGAAUCAGUCUCAGGUCACUUUACCCAAAAACAUUUGAAAAUCUGAACCACAAUCUCCUGAAAGUUUUUCUCCUAUAGAUUGUUGACAACACAUUGUUUUCUGGAGGCAUUUGUGCCAUUAGGUUUCCAUUUAUCUUCAGUUUUUUUCUUUGGUGUUUGGGAUGUCUUAUUUUGUUGCCUUAUGUCCUUUUCAAUUUAAAAUGUUUGAGUUUGUAUAUAGUUUUGAAAUUGGAUUAUGUGUUCAUUGUUGUUUAGUUUGCAUUUUUGUCAAAUUAUGGUUUUGAAGGUUCAUUUGGAACUUACUGUUAGUCUGUAACAGGGUUGCCCUUGUCCAGUAUUUAUUUAUAAGCUGUUUACUUUUCAAGUUGAUAAAAACAUUCUCCAAUUCUAAAUUUGCUUGUGUCCAUAGGUGAUCUCUUUAGCAAACUGAGAAAAAAAGGAAGCUACUUUUAACAUGCAAAGUUCCCUCAAGGUGUACCGUGUUGUCUCUGUGGGCACUCUUCCCCAGCACUUUAGCAGUAAUUCCCCCAGCUACACGCUGCAGUUGUACUCUGCCCACUCUAGUGUUCCUCAGCUCUGCUGUCCUUUUACUUGUAGCUGGAUCUUUGAUUAUCCUUCGAUUUCCAUGAAAUAUUAAUAUUGUUGCCAGCAUAGCAGGUACAGUGGAAGUCUUGUAGCAGUGAGAUUGUAUCAUAAUUUAGGAUUUAAAAUGAAUUAAAGUUUAUAUAAACUGAAGAGUCUCCAUAUGUCAAACUCUUGGAAAAUCAAAGAUGUUCCAAUUUCCUAAACACUAGAGAAUACGAGAGAAGGUAGAGUGGAAAAGGUUAGGUAACCUUGCAAAAUAUUUUACUAUUUUCUCUAAAUAUGAGGAAGUUUGAGAUUAUGAUCUGGAUCUACCAGAUAUAACUAAGGUUAAUUUAGCAUGAAAAAGUUUUAGUCAUAUUGGCAUCCAACCUAUUCAGUAACCGAAUCAUAGGACAAUGAUGGAUUAGGAGAACAAUAGAGUGGGAUCAUUAUAAAGAAAAUAAAUUAUUAAAGGUGUCUUUAUCGUUUUAGUGCCAUUUUUAGUGUCUUUACUAUAAAUCAAUAUCAGUGUAUUUUAUCAUUCUAUGUGCAUAGCAGAAUUUUCUUUUCUCCCUUUUGUUCCCCUGUGAACUUGGUGCUUAUUAAAGUGCUCACUGUUCUCUUAAAAGAGAGCAGUGGUAUAGGUGUGCAGUUUCCAUGAUGCAGGUUCCAUUUUUAAUAUAUUGUUCCACUUAUCCUUUCUUCUGAGUAAAUUGCUAAUUGUGCCAAAUUUAUGUAAUAGUUUUUGUAAUGUGGAAUAAGAAUUAUGAUGGAACCAUUGCACAUUUUUUUCUGAAACAGCCAGUCAAGGCAGAACAUUAAUCUCCAAAUGCAAGGGCUGAUCUAUUUAUUCAUUUUGGAGGUUGGGUACUUUAUUCUUUCUUUCCGUCAUCCUUUUCAUUGUUUCCCCCGGAUUCUAAUUAGUUUUUAUUUUUUUUAGAUAACUCCAAUAUAAUCAUUACAGUUUAUGCUUUAAAUACUAUGUGCUUUAAAAAGGAAAAUGGGACCAAUUUGUCUGCUAAGAAUUUGAUUUUAGGUACUAUAAGAGUAUUAGGAAAAUAUAUACAACUGGUGUUAAUUUCUAGAUAUUUUCUAGAAAUCACUUGUGUUCCUAUUUAAUAAAAGGUAAUUUAGAAUACUACUUGUCCUUUGCAGUAGUUUAGUAAUGGGCAUUAAGCUGUGUCCUCGAAGGAUGUACCUAUUACUAGGUGCAUUUUAGAAUGAAAUAUUGAUAUUUUAUUAGCAUAUAAUUGUGGCCAUAUAUCUCAGAUUUUCUGAGGCAGAUCUAAUUUUAGAUAAUUCUGUUGGUAGACCAUGUGAUCCUUCUUUUUGGUUUUGGAAAUAUAAUCAUUGUUAAUGUUUUCCCUCCAAAUAGAAUACUGUUUUAUCCAUACAAAUCAUAACAGCAUCUAUCCCAUGCUAGGGUUGGAAACUGAUAUUGGUAUUACUUGUGUUUUUUCUUAGUGUGUUUUAUUUCCCAGUUUCAUCUUCUUCUAAAAAUGAAAAUAUGGUGCCUUCCCUCCCUCCAGGAAGACUGGCAAAUAUUUCCUUUUAUUUACUGCUGCUGUGGAGUGAUGAGAUAUGCACUUUACUCUUUAAGAUUCAGCAAAAAGCUUUUCACUUCUCAGUAUAUCCAGAAUACAUCAUAUCUGGGACUUAGGAAAAUUUGCCAAGCAAUCUUUGUUUUUAUAGAUACUAAUGUUGACCCUCUCCAGCGUUCAAUGUUAUAAAUAGAACAAGUCAAGCUAGUGUUUAUCUCCUCCCCCUCCCCAAAACUGUGGCACAGCAUAUAAAAAUGUACCUCAAUAAUGUUCUAUUAAAAAUGGGACAGGGGCCUUAUGUUUUCAUAAUUUCCCAACAAUGUGCCGCCAUAUUUUUGCCUCAAGGUAAAGGUUUUAACAGAUGAAAAAGUACUUCCCAAUUCCCCCGUGCUAUUCCUAACCUAUAAUGCCCAAAUGUUUUGUGCAAUGUGUAGUGUGUGUGUAUAAAUACAUAUAUUCUUGAAAUAGACAUACCAUCAGAGACAUCAUUCACAAGUAACUGAUGUAUUGGCAUCUCAUUCAUAUUUCUGAUGUGUGAGGUAUAUGGUACUAAUUACCUUUUCCUUGAUGUUUGCCAAAUUUGAAUAAAGGCAUUGGUACGAAAUUACAGAAUGUAAAGAAAAUGUUUUUGGCUUGAAAAAUUAACAUAUUUUAUGACGUACCACAGUAUACUCUGCCCAAACCAGCACCCUAUCUAUCUUUCCUGUUCUUUACAUCCCUGUUCCCCAUCCCUACUUCCUCAUUUUUGGUAUAACACAGUUCUUUUGUAGCAUCAUUAUAAUUGCAGUUCUAUGGCAAUUGGACAGUUAUAGCAUGGAAACAGACUGGUAUAAGUAGUACAGUAGUCACCAGUGUGCCACAUUUGCAUUAGUAAUGCAAAAUAUACAUUUUAUAAAGGACAAACUUUGUGUUAUGUUUUAUUUUCAUUACAUUGUAUAAUAUUGUAAGACUAUUGUAUGUCCUAAUUUGCAUUAUAAAUGUUUUUUUCCUACGUAAAGGCAUAAAUAUAGCAACUUUGUAUAAAGGUAGCUUAUUAGAUUUUUAAUUUUUUCUUUUAUAAAAAAUUGUCCAACAGUGGGACUACCAUUGCCAAAUUGUAUAUGAAAUAUGAAUUUUACCCCCAUGGUUAAUUUCUUUUAUAAACAUUCCAUAUUUCUCUAAUAAAAAGACAUAAGUGAUACUGUACUAUGCAUACAUUGUAUCUUAAUGCUGUUUCAGAUCAGCAUUUUAAAUUUUGGUUUGCAUUUUUAAUAUUGGCAAAACGUAACCACUGUUAAUUAAAAUAAAACCUUGUUGUAUAUGUAACAACAUAAUUUUCCCUCUAUCCCUUCCCACCCUUUGUUCUCUAUUUCUCCCUAUCAGUGCCAACUUCAUACAUUUUGUAGCAUGGCAAUAAAAUAUAACUUUUACACUGAGGCCGAGUGUGGCUUUUUGGAGGAAGUGGGGAUGGGACGAUUGCCCUCUAGUUGUCCUUUGCAUAUGACUGUUUUUUGCCAUAUAAGCCAUGUCAUCAGGCAUGAAAAGUUUUCUCAUAUAUGAUGUAAACUUGCUUUUAAGGACAAGUGUGAAUGUGCUUUUUAAGCUUAAUUUUUGUCAUGACAACUAAUUUUUUUUAUCUUUGGAGAAGUCAGAGUUCUUUACAAUCAAACGUUUAUUAACUGGAGUACUUAGAAUAAGCUAGUAAUUGAAUUUAGUUCAAGGGCUAAGCAACACAUUUUUAAAUCCUUAUUUAUUGUAGAGUAUUAGUAUACUGUCCUACAAAUUAUGUAAAAUAUGGUUUAAUAUUAGAUGACUUUGGAUUUUGCAAUGCCUUACUGUUGUCAUUCUAGCAUAAAUAUCCAUAAUGAGGUACUCAAGUUGAUACUGGAAGCUGAGCUGAUCAUACACUGACCUGAAGCAUUCAUGAAAAGCUGCUUUAUUGAAUAAAGUCUGAUUGGAGUUCUUUUCAUGCUCACUUUCCCCUUAUUGCUGAAAGUAGAUUGCAAUAAAACCCCAAUAAAACGUUUGGUCGGAUAUCUACUUAAAA